AAAAGCCGGACAAGCUGGGGGCGGCAGAGAGGAGUGAGAAACUCUUGGGGGCGGUGGGCAGAAGAGACCACGCGCCUCAGAAUUCCGCUCGACUUCAUCCACUCCCAGCAUCUUCGAAAGACUUCUUGUCUUCCAAAAUCUGAGAGAGAAUUUUCUCUUCUCUCAAACAUUGCCAGAAACUUACGCUGUGGCCUGGAGAGACUGAGGGAAUAAUGAAAACUUUUCAGCCGUGCCGUAUAUUUCUUUCCCUUACCCCCAACCCGCAUGCAAAGUUAGACAUUUCUAAGUUGAUGCCUUAUCAGUGGAAAAAUGUUGAAGAAAAAUAGGAUCUUUUAUGGAAAAAUCAACUCAUCUCUCACCGGAUGGUAGGGGGCUGAAGAAGAGAAGAAAAUUUCUGUGACUGGCUCCCGACAGGAAUGUUGCGUUUCUGCCUCUUUGGGGUGAAAUCUCUUUCGUCUUGCAUGGCUUUCAUUUCUUAUCAUAAUAUUUAUUUAUUAAGGCCUCGGGUUUCCAAUUCCAUUUAAAUCCAGGUCAGAAUUGCAUUAAAAUAACAAAGUAGAAUUCCAGGCCGGGGAGCUCUGACAGAUCCCUCUAGGAAUUAAAGAGAGACAGGGAGGCCUCCCGCCCCCGUCCCUGACCCCCAGCUCAUCGCCUGGCAGGUCCCAAGGCUGUGCAGGCAGAGACUAGGCUGAUGUACUACAGUUCUCUCGGGACAGUUUCUCCUCCCCCUUGACCUCUUGCUGUACCCCUCCCCCAUCGUGUCCUCACCGACAAGAGAUUUAUAUGGACAAAAAGAAAAUUCCUCCUGGCAAGGUUUUGCCCAGGAGAGUAUGAUUCUGCCUAUUGUCCCAGGGGCUCCUGAAGCCAGCUGGGUGAGGAGAUGGCUGGGCCAGAAGGAAAGUUGAACUUGGGAGUUGGGGAAGCCUGAGUGUCCGACACAGGUCGCUGUGUCCCAGAGCCUGAGCGUUUGGCUCUUAAGCUGCUCUGUUGUAUUGGAUGGGCUCCUGCUCUGUGAAGAGGAAGGUGCUGUAUCAAUGCCGCCCUCCUCUCCCCAAACACUGCCUCUUCAGCUAACCUCUUCCCCCUCCAACCUGUCCUUUCACAGAACUGAAACACUAGAGAUCCUCAGCUGUCAAAUACUGGACCCUGCCCCCACACCUUCCAGCCCCACACUGCCUCUUUUCCAGUCCUGGUUCCAGACAGCGCAUCGCCACUGCCACCCCCAACCUGGGAGCAGCCCCUCUCCUCACUGUGGAUUUGUGUUUUCAUAAACAAAGCUGGCUUUUGUAGUGUGUGCUGACUUACUCAUAACAUGGAAUUAGGUGGGGAGUUUAGUCUGAAGGAAGGAACAGAUAUCAUGAAGUAACCUAGAGACAAGAUAAGGGCCUCUUUCAAGUUGGAGCCAGUGUCUGUAGUGGCCUAGUGAGGCUGUGGACCAAAGGAGAAGCAGUGUAUUCGAGGGGGGCCCAGGGGCAGAUGGAGACCCCUCCAAGGGACAGGUGCCAUCAAGCCAAGGCACUCAAGUAUGGGAGAUCAGCUCAUGAUUCAGGAACGGGAGUCAGAAUCCCUGCAUGGUACUCCAGGGCUUCCACUUUCAUUGGACUCCCUGCUGGGUACUGAGGAACAUGCUGCCAGAGUGAAGGCCCCUGCCCUCAAGGAACUUAGAGUAGUUUUUGUCCCCAGCUUAUCUCAUUCACAGGCCACCCUUCCUGUGACUGGACCGCAGUUAGCUUGGUAUCCUCCUUCUUUUCUUCUGAUCCCUAAGCUUGGCCUAGAAUGGAAGCCUUUCAUUGACCCUUCUCUUCAGGAAAUCUACAAACCCCAUCUGCCAGAGGUUGCCUAAUAGCAGGUUUGCUGGGUUACAGGGAUGUCUCUGGACACAAACUUGCAGGCAGAUGCUGCAGGAAGAACUAGUACUGACCAGGCGGGGCAACCUUACAGCCUUACCCAUAGACACAGUCUGUGAGCAUCAGGGAGGCCUUACCUUCAAACAUAUCUCCUGGUUAUCAGCAGUGCCAGAAAGUGUGCCUUUAAUGCCACAUGCUUUAUAUAAAGCACUAGCAGGUCUUUAAAAUCAAAUACCCUUGGCAAGUAUCUUGCACGGAGUUACUAUACCUCUGGGGGUAUCUGGGUUUCUGUCCCUUUUCAUCAGUGAUUCCCACAAUGGGAAAACCAAAGUCAUGUGGAAGGGGGGAAAGGGGGAGACAAGGAAGGGAGCCCUAAGUGUAAAGGUGAGUGUGCGACUGUGCACACAUGAGAGGUUCACCACAGUUACCCACAGGCAACAUAGCUGGAUGUCUGUGUUUCUUGUGACGUAGUUGCUAAGGGUAAACUGCUGUUUUAGUGUCUGUGAGAACUGUAUGGAAGAGUAGGUGGGUAAGCCUGUGUGACUGGGAAGGGAGGGAGCAUGAGGGGACAUGGUUUUGAGUGUUUUUCAAGUGCUUGUCUGUAUAUUUUAAAGUAGACAGACUGGAUAACCAAGAUAAUUGUUAACUUAAAAGCAUUAAUUUGCUUUGCUUUUGGUAAGGGGGUGGGUGUUUGGCGGGGGGGGGGGGGGCGGGGGGGAGGCGCGGCGGGGGGGGGGGUGUGUGCAGCAGUGGUUAAAAAGACCUAAUCCUCGCAUAGGGCUCAGGUUACAGCUGAAUGAAAAGGUCUCUCGGCCUCCAGGGAAACUUGUCCCCAGGGCUGGCUCCAGGAGAGCCAGCCUGGCCGUUUAGUUUACCUGGUAGUUUUCUCUCCUUGUUAGGGAUAGAGUUUUGAUAAAGUCAUGCAUUUAGAAUUUCCAAGUAACCCCAUCCCUGGGACUGAGAGCGUUCAUGUGGUGGCAAACAGUGUCUCUCUGUCUCGGUGUGUCUCUCCGGGUCUCUGUCUGGGUGUAUGUGUCUCUUUCUUUCUCCCACCCUUCUCUUCCUCUUUAAUGUGGCUGUUUCCUUUCCUCCCCGCUUCCCUGGGCUCCUGUGGCCAGCUCUUACAGUGAGGGGACUGUUCCUACUAGCCCCUCCCUCCAAAAUAUGAAAUGAAAACCAUAACCAUGUCAGCGGGUAAGGGUGGCCCCGUGGGCAGCCGGCUAUUGCCUGUGCCCUGUCCAGGCCACACUGGAGAGAGGGAGAGUCCCCACUCAGAGCCUGAUCUUUAGUCAGUUCCCUCUAAGCCCACCCCCAUUUUUCCAGAAGGUGGAGAAGAGGGUGGACUGCUUAGAAAUUCCUCAGGAAUCCCUUUGACCUCUCUUCUCUCAUGACAUGUCUCAGAGGUGGGGAAAGCCUCGGGGUGGGAGAGUACAGAGACUUUUCCCUGUUUUCAACCCCUUCCUUCUCAUCUCUUUGAGUCUCUGCAGGGUGGAAUAAGAGAAAGGGGACUAGAAGACACUAAGGCCAGAAUUACUGCAGGCAGAGAAAGAAGACAGUCAUCAGCAGCCCUCAAAUGAGAUUGUUUUUUGAAACCUUCAGGAAUCUGAGAGCAUGAGAACCGGUUUGAGAUGUGAGCAGCUGGGACCUGUUGUAAGAGGAGCCGGCCCUGGGUAUGUGGAUGAGUGUGUGGAGGGGACUGACAACUGCCACAUCGAUGCUAUCUGCCAGAACACCCCGAGGUCAUACAAGUGCAUCUGCAAGUCUGGCUACACAGGGGACGGCAAACACUGCAAAGACGUGGAUGAGUGCGAGCGAGAGGAUAAUGCAGGUUGUGUGCAUGACUGUGUCAACAUCCCUGGCAAUUACCGGUGUACCUGCUAUGAUGGAUUCCACCUGGCACAUGACGGACACAACUGUCUGGAUGUGGACGAGUGUGCCGAGGGCAACGGCGGCUGUCAGCAGAGCUGUGUCAACAUGAUGGGCAGCUAUGAGUGCCACUGCCGGGAAGGCUUCUUCCUCAGCGACAACCAGCAUACCUGUAUCCAGCGGCCAGAAGAAGGAAUGAAUUGCAUGAACAAGAACCACGGCUGUGCCCACAUUUGCCGGGAGACACCCAAGGGGGGUAUUGCCUGUGAAUGCCGUCCUGGCUUUGAGCUUACCAAGAACCAACGGGACUGUAAAUUGACAUGCAACUAUGGUAACGGCGGCUGCCAGCACACGUGUGAUGACACAGAGCAGGGUCCCCGGUGCGGCUGCCAUAUCAAGUUUGUGCUCCAUACCGACGGGAAGACAUGCAUCGAGACCUGUGCUGUCAACAACGGGGGCUGUGACAGUAAGUGCCAUGAUGCAGCGACUGGUGUCCACUGCACCUGCCCUGUGGGCUUCAUGCUGCAGCCAGACAGGAAGACGUGCAAAGAUAUAGAUGAGUGCCGCUUAAACAACGGGGGCUGUGACCAUAUUUGCCGCAACACAGUGGGCAGCUUCGAAUGCAGUUGCAAGAAAGGCUAUAAGCUUCUCAUCAAUGAGAGGAACUGCCAGGAUAUAGACGAGUGUUCCUUUGAUCGAACCUGUGACCACAUAUGUGUCAACACACCAGGAAGCUUCCAGUGUCUCUGCCAUCGUGGCUACCUGUUGUAUGGUAUCACCCACUGUGGGGAUGUGGAUGAAUGCAGCAUCAACCGGGGAGGUUGCCGCUUUGGCUGCAUCAACACUCCUGGCAGCUACCAGUGUACCUGCCCAGCAGGCCAGGGUCGGCUGCACUGGAAUGGCAAAGAUUGCACAGAGCCACUGAAGUGUCAGGGCAGUCCUGGGGCCUCGAAAGCCAUGCUCAGCUGCAACCGGUCUGGCAAGAAGGACACCUGUGCCCUGACCUGUCCCUCCAGGGCCCGAUUUUUGCCAGAGUCUGAGAAUGGCUUCACGGUGAGCUGUGGGACCCCCAGCCCCAGGGCUGCUCCAGCCCGAGCUGGCCACAAUGGGAACAGCACCAACUCCAACCACUGCCAUGAGGCUGCAGUGCUGUCCAUUAAACAACGGGCCUCCUUCAAGAUCAAGGAUGCCAAAUGCCGUUUGCACCUGCGAAACAAAGGCAAAACAGAGGAGGCUGGCAGAAUCACAGGGCCAGGUGGUGCCCCCUGCUCUGAAUGCCAGGUCACCUUCAUCCACCUUAAGUGUGACUCCUCUCGGAAGGGCAAGGGCCGACGGGCCCGGACCCCUCCAGGCAAAGAGGUCACAAGGCUCACCCUGGAACUGGAGGCAGAGGUCAGAGCCGAAGAAACCACAGCCAGCUGUGGGCUGCCCUGCCUCCGACAGCGAAUGGAACGGCGGCUGAAAGGAUCCCUGAAGAUGCUCAGAAAGUCCAUCAACCAGGACCGCUUCCUGCUGCGCCUGGCAGGCCUUGAUUAUGAGCUGGCCCACAAGCCGGGCCUGGUAGCCGGGGAGCGAGCAGAGCCGAUGGAGUCCUGUAGGCCCGGGCAGCACCGUGCUGGGACCAAGUGUGUCAGCUGCCCGCAGGGAACGUAUUACCACGGCCAGACGGAGCAGUGUGUGCCAUGCCCAGCGGGCACCUUCCAGGAGAGAGAAGGGCAGCUCUCCUGCGACCUUUGCCCUGGGAGUGAUGCCCACGGGCCUCUUGGAGCCACCAACGUCACCACGUGUGCAGGUCAGUGCCCACCUGGCCAACACUCUGUAGAUGGGUUCAAGCCCUGUCAGCCAUGCCCACGUGGCACCUACCAACCUGAAGCAGGACGGACCCUAUGCUUCCCUUGUGGUGGGGGCCUCACCACCAAGCAUGAAGGGGCCAUUUCCUUCCAAGACUGUGACACCAAAGUCCAGUGCUCCCCAGGGCACUACUACAACACCAGCAUCCACCGCUGUAUUCGCUGUGCCAUGGGCUCCUAUCAGCCCGACUUCCGUCAGAACUUCUGCAGCCGCUGUCCAGGAAACACAAGCACAGACUUUGAUGGCUCUACCAGUGUGGCCCAAUGCAAGAAUCGUCAGUGUGGUGGGGAGCUGGGUGAGUUCACUGGCUAUAUUGAGUCCCCCAACUACCCGGGCAACUACCCAGCUGGUGUGGAGUGCAUCUGGAACAUCAACCCCCCACCCAAGCGCAAGAUCCUUAUCGUGGUACCAGAGAUCUUCCUGCCAUCUGAGGAUGAGUGUGGGGACGUCCUCGUCAUGAGAAAGAACUCAUCCCCAUCCUCCAUUACCACUUAUGAGACCUGCCAGACCUACGAGCGUCCCAUUGCCUUCACUGCCCGUUCCAGGAAGCUCUGGAUCAACUUCAAGACAAGCGAGGCCAACAGCGCCCGUGGCUUCCAGAUUCCCUAUGUUACCUAUGAUGAGGACUAUGAGCAGCUGGUAGAAGACAUUGUGCGAGAUGGCCGGCUCUAUGCCUCUGAAAACCACCAGGAGAUUUUAAAGGACAAGAAGCUCAUCAAGGCCUUCUUUGAGGUGCUAGCCCACCCCCAGAACUACUUCAAGUACACAGAGAAACACAAGGAGAUGCUGCCAAAAUCCUUCAUCAAGCUGCUCCGCUCCAAAGUUUCCAGCUUCCUGAGGCCCUACAAAUAGUAACCCUAGGCUCAGAGACCCAAUUUUUUAAGCCCCCAGACUCCUUAGCCCUCAGAGCCGGCAGCCCCCUACCCUCAGACAAGGAACUCUCUCCUCUCUUUUUGGAGGGAAAAAAAAAAUAUCACUACACAAACCAGGCACUCUCCCUUUCUGUCUUUCUAGUUUCCUUUCCUUGUCUCUCUCUGCCUGCCUCUCUACUGUUCCCCCUUUUCUAACACACUACCUAGAAAAGCCAUUCAGUACUGGCUCUAGUCCCCGUGAGAUGUAAAGAAACAGUACAGCCCCUUCCACUGCCCAUUUUACCAGCUCACAUUCCCGACCCCAUCAGCUUGGAAGGGUGCUAGAGGCCCAUCAAGGAAGUGGGUCUGGUGGGAAACGGGGAGGGGAAAGAAGGGCUUCUGCCAUUAUAGGGUUGUGCCUUGCUAGUCAGGGGCCAAAAUGUCCCCUGGCUCUGCUCCCUAGGGUGAUUCUAACAGCCCAGGGUCCUGCCAAAGAAGCCUUUGAUUUACAGGCUUAAUGCCAGCACCAGUCCUCUGGGGCACAUGGUUUGAGCUCUGGACUUCCCACAUGGCCAGCUUUCUUGUCUAUACAGAUCCUCUCUUUCUUUCCCUACGUCUGCCUGGGGUCUACUCCAUAAGGGUUUACAAAUGGCCCACAACACUGAGUUAGUGGACACCGGCUAAAUGAGGAAGAGCAGCAGGCAUUGUCAUGGUGAAUGCCCCGCUGUAGCUCCCUGAGAGAAAGACUGUAACUCUGCAGGACAGAAACAAGGUUUUAAAGCAUUGCCAAAAAAAAGAAAACAGAAAGAAAAAAUGUAUCAUCUAAAGGACUAGACACAGAACAAUUGGAAGUCAACUUCAAACACUAAUCCCUUUUCUUGUCUUCCCUGGCCCAGCCACCUCCUCAGCCCCAUGUGAUGCUCCCUGGGGGAGCCCUACUCCCCUUGCUACAUGUUGUCCUUAAACAUGGUUAUUGACCUGAAGCCAGCCUAGGCCUUGCCCUACAGUUGUUUUUCCCUUGUAGCCCCAGCUGGCUUGUGGGCUUCACCAAAGAGGACCCCACUCUGAAGCCAGCCUGGAGCCACCUACCUCUGGCCUCAGGCUGUGGGCAGCAAAAGGAAUGUGUGUGCACUUGGCGAGCCUCCUGCCCACCCUGUCCACACCUAAUAAGUGCAAUCAUUUUGAGUCUUUCUAUGUUGUCUAGACGGAGGGGUUUUUGUUUUCUGGGUUUGUUUUUUGUUUUUGUUUCUUCUUCCUCUAUUAGCAAAACCCUAUUUAUAGCUGCCCAAGAGAAAAGAGUGUAUGUUUGGAGUGGAAGAAAAUCGGUUUUGAAUCUCAUGAACCUUGAGUGCUGGAGCAUCUGAUCUGUCUCUAUGCCACCACUGGCCACCUAGAGCCCUUGGCUGUGGUAAUCCAGGGUAAUUGCGCAGAGGCAUCUGAUGUGUAGGAAAGUAAUUCUGGGGAUUUGAUGGAGCAGAAAGGAGAGAGACCUAUGUUUGCUAAACCAAUCUUGCUAUCCCUAUGCCUCUCCAUGGAGUCAGUGUGGACCUCAUGAUUAUAGAGGCCAAUGGAACUGGUCAGUGAUUCUCUACCCCAAGUAGGGAAAACCUCCAUCUUUUCCCUGUCUUCAUCCUGUUAUCCCCUGGUGUACACAUGGAAGAGGACCAGGACAUACCACCUGGGGAUGGGCUGACUCAGGGUCCCGAGGCCAGAGACAAAGCUGUGGGAGCCAAGAAUAAGACAGAAGGCAUCAGAUAUUUGCCUGGCUCUGGUCACUUCCCUUUGAAGUUGACUUCAAGCUUAGCUUCCUCAACUACUGUUUUUCAGAAGGAAGAAAGAAUCAAAUGGAAGAAGAAUCAAGUCCAUGCCCAAGCCCAAAGCCUGCACACAUUCUGCCCUUAAUCCAAGUGUUGCCUAUAAAAUUAUUUUCUGUUUUCUCACUCUAGUUCCCCCAAAGCUGUAGUCCCAAUCAAUCAAAGGCUACCAACUGAGUCCUCAGGUUCAUUUCUUUUUUUUUUUUUUUUCUUUUUAACUCUCCUGGUAACUCACAGAACAGCUCAGGUUCAUUUCUAGGUGACUGUCCUAGGCUACUGCUCCCCCAGGAGACUCAACACUAAAUAAAGGAGUCUGACUCCCUGCCCUCCCAUCAGUAGCAUUCAUCAGCCAAAACGGCCAUAGCAGUAGGUAGCCAAUGACACAGCUAGAUUCCCUGACAACCAUUAGCCAACAUCAUGGUCCUUGUGGGUAGAGUGUCUGGCUACCUUUGUCUUUCUGGGUCAAGGAGGGCCACUGUAAAGAUGCAAAAUGGCUGCUUCCAAACAAGGGAAAUGGUCAUUUAGUAUGAGUGUCUCUGUACUUCCCAGGAAGCACCAUGAAAACUGCUUUAAUCAACUCUGACUAUCCUAAUUCUCCACCAGAAGCUAGGAUAACUUUCUUUCUUUCUUUCUUUUUUUUUUUUUUUUUUUUUGAGAUGGAGUCUCGCUCUGUCACCCAGGCUGGAGUGUAAUGGUGCUAUCUCGGCCUACUGCAACCUCCGCCUCCCAGGCUCAAGCAAUUCUGCCUCGGCCUCCCAAGUAGCUGGGAUUACAGGCAUGCGCCACCGCGCCCAGCUAAUUUUUGUAUUUUUAGUAGAGAUGGGGUUUCACCAUGUUGCCCGGGCUGGUCUUGAACUCUUGACCUCAGGUGAUCCACCCGCCUCAGUCUCCCAAAGUGCUGGGAUUACAGGCAUGAGCCACCGCGCCCAGCCUAGGAUAACUUUCUGAUUCCUCUCUGCCAGCCGUUUUGCGUCUCUUGGAAAGCCAAACGGUGACCAUGCUUCUUAAUUUAUGCCUUCAGGGUCUGGCUUCUCCUUUCUCCCUUCCUUUCCUGUCACACCAUGCAUACAUACAUACAAAUACACAUCCUUCAACCAUUUAUUCCAUGGCUUAUGAGACCUGCAAAUGAGUUCCACAGUACGGAAGGCAUAGACCACUAGGCUUCUUAAUUGAUGUCAAGGCAGAUCUUGGUGAGCAGGUAAAAACCUGCUAUUGUCCACCAAGUUUAAUUUAGGUCCUCCAAGUUGGAGGGUUAAGAACCCAGGCAAAGCUGCUGCUGAAUCUAUGGAGGAGGCUGGCCCUGGGACAUCAAACUAGGGGUUAACUGGAUUGAAUGAGGAGUCAACGCUCAGGGACAUUCUAGGUCUUUACAGGUCAGACAGAAGAGAGGUUUUUACCAUUGGAGGGAAAUGGAAAGAUGGUAUAAAUAGGAUCCCUUCAUGAAGCAACCCAGAGGCCUCUCUGCAGCGUGUAGGGUGUGGGGCGACAGUAUUGUGGGGCUUCCAUUCAUCUUAGUACAAAACCUCACCUGCUCUGAGCCUGGAAAUGGGAGGGCUUCACGCACCAAGUAAUGCACACCAGAAAGGCACUUAUAUCCUCAGCAACAUGGCAGUUCCUCUUUACUUCUCUGCCUCCCUCUUUCUAUAUUAUCAGGCCAUGCCUAUUCCUACAACCUGAGACAACUCUUGGAGUCAGAAGAAAACUGACCAGAUCCUGGAUCUGAGCUGCCUGCUCCAGGCCUAGAAAUCCCCAAAGGCUGGCACUGAGCUGUGACUGCUUUAACAGCCCCCAAGAUUUGGUCAGUUUGAGGUGGUGGAGACUCAGAUUUGUUGCUGAAAGUUCAGUAACACAGUCCUGGUCUUUGGCCCUAGAGAAACUUUUUAUAUGAGAAGUGUUCUCUAUAUACAUGUUUGAGGUGACUCUGGAAUGGAUUAUGAGGUCAUAUCUCAAAAUGUCAGAAAACGUUAUAGAGCACUCGAACUUUUGUAUUUGCUGCUUAACCUCAAUAUUACAGCCACAAACAAGGGGUACCAAGACAAAGUAUAACUGAGCAUAAGCAGAAAAUGUUAACCCUCCAGGUUUCUUUCUUAAGCACAAUAAAAGUGGGAGCGAACAACACAAGGAUAUUUUUACAUUUGACCCGUCUCAAAAGUAGCACACCCUAUCCUUGUGCCAUUAUUUGUACAAGGAAAUAUAUGAUUAGAAGGAAUAGAACCCCCAGUUGUCAUCAGCUUUUUUAGACACCACAGGUUGUAGCAGUUUGAACAAACUGAAAACUUUAUACUUCUGUGUGAGCUGAACUCAAGUUUCAGAAUAAUCAUCGCCAUGUGGGAGGCUUUUUGUUAAAUGCAGAAGAAAUUUCAAAAUAUUGUAUUUAUAUCUGCCUUCCACUGCUGCCAAUUUAGUAAGCAUCUCCUAUACAAUCGACAAUAAACAGCAAAUGAUGCAGUUCAUAGAGUAUUUUGCACUUGGGGAAAAAUAUGUAUCUGAAUUGUAAAAAGAAAUGUUUGGAUUUUGUAUGUCUUUUUUAUUAUUAUUAAAAUACUAAAUGAAACUCCUCA